GUGGUGCGAGCGCUGCACCAGCCCCUGGCUGGUGGUUACUGUCCGAACGGCGUGGUGUGGUCGCUGACUCUCUGGGCGUGCAGCUCCGCAGCCCUGCCGGCUCGGUUCGGUUCGUGAGCGGCCGGGAUUGACUUACGCAGGAUUCUCAGCCCUUGCCUGGGAGAACAGUUCAGGAGACAGAUGGCCCCAAGAGCCCAGAUCCAGGGACCGCUGACAUUUGGGGAUGUGGCUGUGGCCUUUACCCGGAUUGAGUGGAGACACCUGGAUGCUGCUCAGCGGGCCCUGUACAGGGAUGUGAUGCUGGAGAACUAUGGGAAUCUGGUGUCUGUGGGGCUUCUCUCUUCCAAACCAAAACUAAUUACUCAGUUGGAGCAAGGGGCAGAGCCCUGGACUGAGGUGCGAGAGGCUCCAUCAGGCACACAUGCAGUCGAGGAUUACUGGUUUGAAACAAAGAUGUCAGCCCUAAAGCAAAGCACUUCUGAAGCAUCUGUUCUGGGAGAGCGAACGAAAAGUGUCAUGAUGGAAAAAGGCCUGGACUGGGAGGGCAGAAGCUCCACAGAGAAGAACUAUAAGUGCAAGGAAUGUGGGAAAGUCUUCAAAUACAAUUCGUCCUUUAUUAGCCACCAGAGAAAUCACACCAGUGAGAAACCACAUAAAUGUAAAGAAUGUGGGAUCGCCUUUAUGAACAGUUCAUCCCUUUUAAAUCACCAUAAGGUUCAUGCAGGCAAACAGCCUUAUAGAUGUAUUGAAUGUGGGAAGUUCCUGAAGAAGCACUCAACGUUUAUCAACCAUCAGAGAAUUCAUUCUAGGGAGAAACCCCACAAAUGCAUUGAAUGUGGAAAAACUUUCAGAAAGAACUCAAUCCUUUUAAGUCAUCAGAGAAUUCAUACUGGCCAGAAACCCUACAAAUGUAAUGACUGUGGGAAAGCCUUCGCUCAGAAUGCAGCUCUUACUCGUCAUGAAAGAAUACAUAGUGGAGAGAAGCCUUUUAAAUGUAACAAGUGUGGGAGAGCUUUCAGGGAUAAUUCAACUGUGUUGGAACAUCAGAAAAUCCAUACUGGUGAGAAGCCAUAUCAGUGUAAUGAAUGUGGAAAAGCCUUUAGGAAGAGCUCAACUCUUAUUAGUCACCAAAGAAUGCAUACUGGGGAGAAACCCUAUCACUGCAGUAAAUGUGGAAAAUCUUUCAGGUAUAGCUCAUCCUUUGCUGGUCAUCAGAAAACUCACAGUGGAAAUAAACCGUAUCAGUGUCGUGACUGUGGGAAGGCCUUUACAAAGAGCUCAACCCUUACUGGACAUCAGAGAAUUCAUACUGGAGAAAAACCCUAUCACUGUAAGAAAUGUGGGAAAGCCUUUCGGCACAGCUCAGGCCUUGUUGAACAUCAGAGACUCCAUACUGGGGAAAAACCUUAUAAAUGUAAUGAAUGUGGGAAAGCUUUUCCCCGAAGUUCAGCCCUUAAGCAACAUAAGAAAAUUCAUAAUAAAGAAAGAGCCAUGAAAUGUAGUUAGUGUGGCAAAUUGUGCAGAGUAGUUUAUUCCUUCUGACCAUCAUAGAGGAGACAUUAAAUAAAUUAUGCAUUUAACAGAAAUACUCUGUACUUCUGAGAGAACACAUCACUUGUGAGGAUAUUCAUUGUGAGGUUCUACUAGUGAAAUAUUUGAAGAAACUAAAUGUAUGUCAGUAUGGAAGUAGUUAUAGCAUACUGUGUGCUAAUUGAAAAGAAUGAGGUGGAGCUGUAAAUACUGUACAAAGCCAGGCAUGGUGGCAUAUGCCUGUAGUCCCAGUUACUUGGGAGGCUGAGACAGGAUUGCUUAAGCCCAGGAGUUUGAGUCUGUAAUGCACUAUGAUUGUGCAUGUGAAUAGCCACUGCACUCCAGCCUGGGCAACAUAGCAAGACUCCAUCUCUAAGUAAAAAAAUACAACAGUAGAAAUAUACCCAUGAUAAUAUACCCAAUAUACCCUUGUUAAAGAAGCAAGUUUCAGGAAAUCUAUAUUAUAUGCAUUCAAAAAGACCUGGACAAAUAAAGACCAAUCUUAACAGCA